UGCUGUGUGCUUGCCACUCCCACACAAGAGGCAAGGCUUUCUGACUUUUGCUGGCAUUCCUUAUAGUCAGAAAAGCUGCUUAAAGGGGCCUAGAAGAGGAAUCGCUGAGUGAGUUUAAGAUAAAUGUAAAUGACCUACUUUCUCUGUCUUCCAUUUGAAAAUAAUCUACCUUAAGGCUCAGGGGGAAGUGGAGACAGGUCCUGCCCUUGGAGAGGAAUGCUGAUUUCAUCUAUUCUUAUUCUUUAUUCUAUGCUAGAGGGAAUUAGAUUUUCCUUUGUGAUAGUGAUAAAUUUGUGAUGACCAUGUAGGCACCAUAGCAACUGAUUUUUACGUAGUCUCUCAUUUAGCCUUCUCUACUUUCUCGUAAAGCUGUGUACUCAUAGUCUGAAACAUAUUAAGGCACUUGCCUGAUGUUGCACAAGUGAAAAGGACUGAGCCAGAAUUUGAACCCACAAAUGUCUGAUUGCAGCAUGGCAGGUGCAGAUUCUGUGCUGACCCGAGUGUCUUCCAGUGACCUUAGCCCUGACAUAGCCCCAGGAUGGCCUCUCUAGCCUGCUAGACCUGCUGGAGACAGCCCUGGAUCCAGGGCAAGGAUGUGGGUGGAAAGCAGCCUGCAGAAAGGUUGGCAUGACAUUCUGAUGGGAGCCUGGCAUUGCAGCUGUCUAUGGAAAGUCUCUUCUGGAAAUAAACAGAAGAAAGAAUUCAACCGCUAGUUGUGUCAGCUGUCUUUGUAGGAUCUUGUGUACAGUGUAAUCAUAGCCCUCACUCAGUGGAAAGGGAGGGCUGUGCUUCUGAGCCUGACCUUUAGAAUUGUUUUUCUAAGGCAGCACAGUCUAAAUCAACAACUACAGAGAAGAUUGGCUGUGCUAUGCAGUUGUACUUUUAAAUAUCCAAUGUACUAAAUUUAGAAUAAUAGAACCUCAAAAGGUUGGAGGGGACCUCAAAGGUAAGGUGCUUCCCUAUCCAGGCAGAUUCAUGGGCACCUUUUAUAACCCUCUUCACAAGCUGACUUCUUUUAUGUGUUUACUCUUACCUGACCUCAGGUAAUACCUGUUGGAUUCAGCCUUGUAAUUUCUCCAGUAAUCAGGACAUUCUCCCUCCUCUUUGAGGUAUUAUUGUAAGAAAGCUAUUUUUUGGCUACUGGAAUCAAUUUAGUCAGUGGCCCACCAGCCUGAUGACUGUCUCUCUCAGAAAGAAGAAAGUCAACUAUUAUUCCCAUGCAUAUUUCAAAAUAAUAUAAAAGCAAAACAAAACAAAUAAAAACCAAAAAAAAGUCAUUCAUGCUUGUGUAUGGAAUGUAUGGUGGUCCUGUAGGGGUAGAUAUUUAACAGAGACCAACAGGGGAAAAUGGCGUUAGCAAUUAACCUUCUCAAAGAUGCUUGAUGUUCAGUAAACUUAAAACCAUUGUGUAUCCCAUUUUGUAUUUCUCUUCCUCUGCCUCUUAGCAAACCUUCAUAGGAUCCUAAAUACCUUGUUGUCUUUUUCGCCUCCCCAUCUCCCAUCUUUCAUGUCCCACUUUCACAGAAUUGAGCUUUCUGACCUAGCAACAUUCCAGACUGUUCUGUGCACCGCUGUCAGCAAUCGCAGGAUCUGGUGAUAAGUCACAUAUCAGGAGUGCUGUGAGGGCAGUUAUGUCUAGUACUCUUAGUUAAGUAACCUUUAAACUACAGUUAUUUAUCACAACCAUGGUGACAUCACCAAGGGACAUUCUAAUGGAACUUUAAAAAAAUCCAUCUCAAAAUAUUACAGGGAUUGUGAAAUUUGAUGAACUAGUGAAAUGAGAUCCGAGGCUAAAAACAACUUUGAAUCAGAAUAGACCAGAGGACUGCCAUUUCGCCAAAGGAUGCUUUUGAAACUCGGCAGGACUUAAAUGAGGAAGAAGCUGCUCAGGUGCAUGGAGUCAAGGACCCGGCGCCAGCAUCAACCCAGAGCGUGCUUGCCGAUGGGACAGAUUCUGCAGACCCCUCACCAGUCCACAAAGAUGGGCAGAAUGAGGCCGACAGUGCACCAGAAGACCUCCACUCUGUGGGGACCAGCAGGCUGCUCUAUCACAUCACUGAUGGUGAUAACCCACUGCUGUCGCCACGAUGCUCCAUCUUCAGCCAAAGCCAGAGAUUCAACUUAGACCCCGAGUCAGCCCCAUCUCCACCCAGCACUCAGCAGUUUAUGAUGCCGCGGAGUUCUUCACGCUGCAGCUGUGGAGAUGGCAAGGAGCCACAGACCAUCACCCAGCUCACCAAGCACAUCCAGAGCCUCAAGCGGAAAAUUCGGAAAUUUGAAGAAAAAUUUGAACAAGAAAAGAAAUACCGGCCUUCACAUGGUGACAAGACUUCUAAUCCUGAAGUCCUGAAAUGGAUGAAUGAUUUGGCUAAAGGUCGUAAACAGCUCAAAGAACUAAAGCUAAAGCUGUCAGAAGAACAAGGGAGUGCUCCCAAAGGUCCACCUAGAAACCUGUUGUGUGAGCAACCCACAGUCCCCAGAGAAAAUGGGAAACCGGAAGCUGCGGGCCCGGAGCCAAGCUCCUCUGGAGAAGAGACUCCAGAUGCUGCCUUGACAUGCCUGAAGGAGAGAAGAGAGCAACUUCCUCCCCAGGAGGAUUCUAAGGUAACUAAGCAAGACAAGAACCUCAUAAAGCCGCUUUAUGACCGAUACAGAAUUAUCAAGCAAAUCUUGUCAACACCUUCCCUUAUUCCAACAAUUCAGGAGGAAGAGGACUCUGAUGAAGACCGUCCACAGGGAAGCCAACAACCUUCUUUGGCAGAUCCAGCAUCUCACCUUCCUGUUGGUGACCACCUCACCUACUCUAAUGAGACUGAGCCUGUUAGGGCCCUUUUACCAGAUGAAAAGAAAGAAGUAAAACCACCAGCUCUCUCCAUGUCUAAUUUACAUGAGGCUACCAUGCCUGUACUUCUUGACCAUCUCCGAGAAACUAGGGCUGACAAGAAGAGACUGCGGAAAGCCUUAAGAGAAUUUGAAGAACAGUUUUUUAAACAAACAGGAAGAAGUCCACAAAAGGAAGAUAGGAUACCAAUGGCAGAUGAGUAUUAUGAAUAUAAGCACAUAAAAGCCAAACUGAGACUAUUAGAGGUCCUCAUCAGCAAGCAAGAUGUGGCCAAAACUAUUUGAGGUUCAGGAAAUGUUAUGAUCACUUUCACCCAUGAUAUAAAGUAAAGUUUAUUUUCCUCUGCCAUCCUUGCUAAGUAGUUUUGACACAAUGAAAAUGGAAGCACUUUAGUGGUAGUAUUAGCUGUUUUUAAGAAGGAAUAGCAAGUUUAAUUAUAUACAAGGAGAAGGGAUUUAAACGGGGGGAAGAAUACAACAGGUAGCCAUAUAAUUGGGAAAAAAUUCAGUGUCCUCCAUGCCAAGCAGAAAACUCAUAGUCAAUACAAGUAUUUUUAAAAAUGUCUAAUAUUUUAUCAAAUCUAAAUAACAUAGCUAGGACACUUGUUAGGGAAAGUUUAUUUAGUAUCCAAAGACUGUUUAUGUUGAUGUAUGGAAAAGAGCAUGAUUUUAAAAAAUCAAUCAUAGGAGGAAAAGAAAUUCGCUUUUCAAGUAGGAAGGAAUACAGCUAGCAAGAAAGCAAUUUAUUUGAAACUUCUAAUGGAUUUUUGAGUGAUAAAACAUUUACUACCUUGUCCUUUAAGUCUGCUAGGCUCUCAGUACCCUAAAAUAAACUAGAUUGUGUUGCUAUUUUUUUCUUUCUCUAUAAAAAUAACACAUUAUUUUAUCCGUUAUUUGAAAUUUUACAUUUCUGGUUACCAAAGUUCAUUCUGAUAGCAUGUACUUUGUGAAUUAUUAUCUUUGUCUAUAACUGACAGAUGUUUAUAUUAAAAUAAAAUAUUGUAUUAAAAAUUUAAAAUAGGUAUUUUGGAUAGAUAUGUGUCUGUAGUAUAUAAUCUAAUGUGUCCAUAGUAUUAUUGCUAAUCUUUUGGUUUACUAUAAGAUGAUAUAACUAUUUUUUCAUUGGGAAUAUACAUUUUUCUUAAUGUUCCAACAUCUAUACUUUGUAAAGUCAAAACAUUUCCCAUGAGCUGUAGUUAUUCAUCCUUCUGUACAAAAUGAAAAGUUUGGAAAUUGUUUGCCCUGAUACCUUGAAAAAGAAGCCAGAAUAUUUAUUUGCUUCAUCAACUUCAGUGUAUAUCAUUUUGUGUUAUUUUAUACGAAAACAUGUUUAUUAUUUUCAUUUUUGUAAAAGGAAGUAAAAGGUCAACAUUUUCUCUCAUGUACCAACCUUGUUUGUAUUUCUAUUUUCUGUAAUGUUUAAGUAUGAUGUUGAAGAAAUUCACAUUCUCUUAUAGUUUGGAUGGGAAGACUAUUGACUAUUUCAGAAACAGACUUAUUUCAGAGGCUUAUUGUUUUCUCUGUAUUUACCUAAUAUUUUAUAACUUUUAUGAAUCAGAAUAAUGUCCUUCAUAAAUUUGUUUAAUUGAAGUCAUCUACUUCUAACAGGACAGAUACACAACUAUUUGAGGUUUACAAAUUACAUCUUUGAUAAGGGAAAUGGUUUCGUGACAUGUACACAGUUGCUAUUAAAAUGUAACUCUAUAUAUUCUAUAUGAUUGUAAAUAUUUUAUACAACAAUACAAAUAAAAUAUUUUUCUAUUAUAUUUA